AGACGGUGGCCGAGCGGGGGACCGGGAAGCAUGGCCCGGGGGUCGGCGGUUGCCUGGGCGGCGCUCGGGCCGUUGUUGUGGGGCUGCGCGCUGGGGCUGCAGGGCGGGAUGCUGUACCCCCAGGAGAGCCCGUCGCGGGAGUGCAAGGAGCUGGACGGCCUCUGGAGCUUCCGCGCCGACUUCUCUGACAACCGACGCCGGGGCUUCGAGGAGCAGUGGUACCGGCGGCCGCUGUGGGAGUCAGGCCCCACCGUGGACAUGCCAGUUCCCUCCAGCUUCAAUGACAUCAGCCAGGACUGGCGUCUGCGGCAUUUUGUCGGCUGGGUGUGGUACGAACGGGAGGUGAUCCUGCCGGAGCGAUGGACCCAGGACCUGCGCACAAGAGUGGUGCUGAGGAUUGGCAGUGCCCAUUCCUAUGCCAUCGUGUGGGUGAAUGGGGUCGACACGCUAGAGCAUGAGGGGGGCUACCUCCCCUUCGAGGCCGACAUCAGCAACCUGGUCCAGGUGGGGCCCCUGCCCUCCCGGCUCCGAAUCACUAUCGCCAUCAACAACACACUCACCCCCACCACCCUGCCACCAGGGACCAUCCAAUACCUGACUGACACCUCCAAGUAUCCCAAGGGUUACUUUGUCCAGAACACAUAUUUUGACUUUUUCAACUACGCUGGACUGCAGCGGUCUGUACUUCUGUACACGACACCCACCACCUACAUCGAUGACAUCACCGUCACCACCAGCGUGGAGCAAGACAGUGGGCUGGUGAAUUACCAGAUCUCUGUCAAGGGCAGUAACCUGUUCAAGUUGGAAGUGCGUCUUUUGGAUGCAGAAAACAAAGUCGUGGCGAAUGGGACUGGGACCCAGGGCCAACUUAAGGUGCCAGGUGUCAGCCUCUGGUGGCCGUACCUGAUGCACGAACGCCCUGCCUAUCUGUAUUCAUUGGAGGUGCAGCUGACUGCACAGACGUCACUGGGGCCUGUGUCUGACUUCUACACACUCCCUGUGGGGAUCCGCACUGUGGCUGUCACCAAGAGCCAGUUCCUCAUCAAUGGGAAACCUUUCUAUUUCCACGGUGUCAACAAGCAUGAGGAUGCGGACAUCCGAGGGAAGGGCUUCGACUGGCCGCUGCUGGUGAAGGACUUCAACCUGCUUCGCUGGCUUGGUGCCAACGCUUUCCGUACCAGCCACUACCCCUAUGCAGAGGAAGUGAUGCAGAUGUGUGACCGCUAUGGGAUUGUGGUCAUCGAUGAGUGUCCCGGCGUGGGCCUGGCGCUGCCGCAGUUCUUCAACAACGUUUCUCUGCAUCACCACAUGCAGGUGAUGGAAGAAGUGGUGCGUAGGGACAAGAACCACCCCGCGGUCGUGAUGUGGUCUGUGGCCAACGAGCCUGCGUCCCACCUAGAAUCUGCUGGCUACUACUUGAAGAUGGUGAUCGCUCACACCAAAUCCUUGGACCCCUCCCGGCCUGUGACCUUUGUGAGCAACUCUAACUAUGCAGCAGACAAGGGGGCUCCGUAUGUGGAUGUGAUCUGUUUGAACAGCUACUACUCUUGGUAUCACGACUACGGGCACCUGGAGUUGAUUCAGCUGCAGCUGGCCACCCAGUUUGAGAACUGGUAUAAGAAGUAUCAGAAGCCCAUUAUUCAGAGCGAGUAUGGAGCAGAAACGAUUGCAGGGUUUCACCAGGAUCCACCUCUGAUGUUCACUGAAGAGUACCAGAAAAGUCUGCUAGAGCAGUACCAUCUGGGUCUGGAUCAAAAACGCAGAAAAUACGUGGUUGGAGAGCUCAUUUGGAAUUUUGCCGAUUUCAUGACUGAACAGUCACCGACGAGAGUGCUGGGGAAUAAAAAGGGGAUCUUCACUCGGCAGAGACAACCAAAAAGUGCAGCGUUCCUUUUGCGAGAGAGAUACUGGAAGAUUGCCAAUGAAACCAGGUAUCCCCACUCAGUAGCCAAGUCACAAUGUUUGGAAAACAGCCUGUUUACUUGAGCAAGACUGAUACCACCUGCGUGUCCCUUCCUCCCCGAGUCAGGGCGACUUCCACAGCAGCAGAACAAGUGCCUCCUGGACUGUUCACGGCAGACCAGAACGUUUCUGGCCUGGGUUUUGUGGUCAUCUAUUCUAGCAGGGAACACUAAAGGUGGAAAUAAAAGAUUUUCUAUUAUGGAAAUAAAGAGUUGGCAUGAAAGUGGCUACUGAAAA